AUGUUCUAUAUUGGGGCUAGAACUGUGGACCAUAAGCUAAAUUACUCGGUGCCCACCAGCGGCCUCCCCUGUGUCCCUGUGACCGUGGCGGCAAAGACGGACUCAGGAGUGCAAGUUGCUGAUGAAGUAUGUCACAUUUUUUGUGACAUAAAAGUUCAUAAAUGCUCCACAUCAGAAGAAAUCAAGAAAAGAAAGAAGACUGUCAUUUUUUGUCUCAGUGCAGACAAAAAGUGCAUCAUUGUAGAAGAGGGCAAAGAGAUCUCAGCUGGAGAUAUUGGUGUAACCAUAACUGGUCCUUUCAAGCACUUUGUGGGAAUGCUUCCUGAAAAAGAUUGCUGCUAUGCUUUAUAUGAUGCAAGCUUUGAAACGAAGAAAUCCGGAAGAGUAUUGUUUGUUUGUUUGUUUUUGUGGGCACCAGAACUACCACCUCUGAAAAGUAAAAUGAUCUUCACAAGCUGUAAGGAUGCAAUCAAAAAGAAAUUUCAAGCAAAUGGACCAGAAGAUCUCAACUGGGCUUGUAUUGCUGAAAAGUUAGAUGGGUACUUAAUUGCAGCUUUUGAAGGAUGCUCUGUGUAG